ACAGAGCCCGGGCCACAGGCAGCUCCUUGCCAGCUCUCCUCCUCGCACAGCCGCUCGAACCGCCUGCUGAGCCCCAUGGCCCGCGCCACGCUCUCCGCCGCCCCCAGCAAUCCCCGGCUCCUGCGGGUGGCGCUGCUGCUCCUGCUCCUGGUGGCCGCCAGCCGGCGCGCAGCAGGAGCGCCCCUGGCCACUGAACUGCGCUGCCAGUGCUUGCAGACCCUGCAGGGAAUUCACCUCAAGAACAUCCAAAGUGUGAAGGUGAAGUCCCCCGGACCCCACUGCGCCCAAACCGAAGUCAUAGCCACACUCAAGAAUGGGCAGAAAGCUUGUCUCAACCCCGCAUCGCCCAUGGUUAAGAAAAUCAUCGAAAAGAUGCUGAAAAAUGGCAAAUCCAACUGACCAGAAGGAAGGAGGAAGCUUAUUGGUGGCUGUUCCUGAAGGAGGCCCUGCCCUUACAGGAACAGAAGAGGAAAGAGAGACACAGCUGCAGAGGCCACCUGGAUUGCGCCUAAUGUGUUUGAGCAUCACUUAGGAGAAGUCUUCUAUUUAUUUAUUUAUUUAUUUAUUUGUUUGUUUUAGAAGAUUCUAUGUUAAUAUUUUAUGUGUAAAAUAAGGUUAUGAUUGAAUCUACUUGCACACUCUCCCAUUAUAUUUAUUGUUUAUUUUAGGUCAAACCCAAGUUAGUUCAAUCCUGAUUCAUAUUUAAUUUGAAGAUAGAAGGUUUGCAGAUAUUCUCUAGUCAUUUGUUAAUAUUUCUUCGUGAUGACAUAUCACAUGUCAGCCACUGUGAUAGAGGCUGAGGAAUCCAAGAAAAUGGCCAGUGAGAUCAAUGUGACGGCAGGGAAAUGUAUGUGUGUCUAUUUUGUAACUGUAAAGAUGAAUGUCAGUUGUUAUUUAUUGAAAUGAUUUCACAGUGUGUGGUCAACAUUUCUCAUGUUGAAGCUUUAAGAACUAAAAUGUUCUAAAUAUCCCUUGGACAUUUUAUGUCUUUCUUGUAAGGCAUACUGCCUUGUUUAAUGUUAAUUAUGCAGUGUUUCCCUCUGUGUUAGAGCAGAGAGGUUUCGAUAUUUAUUGAUGUUUUCACAAAGAACAGGAAAAUAAAAUAUUUAAAAAUA